ACAGUUACAGUGCAGAAGCAGAAGCAAAAGAAUUAACCAGCUCUUCAGUCAAGCAAAUCCUCUACUCACCAUGCUUCCUCCUGCCAUUCAUUUCUAUCUCCUUCCCCUUGCAUGCAUCCUAAUGAAAAGCUGUUUGGCUUUUAAAAAUGAUGCCACAGAAAUCCUUUAUUCACAUGUGGUUAAACCUGUUCCAGCACACCCCAGCAGCAACAGCACGUUGAAUCAAGCCAGAAAUGGAGGCAGGCAUUUCAGUAACACUGGACUGGAUCGGAACACUCGGGUUCAAGUGGGUUGCCGGGAACUGCGUUCCACCAAAUACAUCUCUGAUGGCCAGUGCACCAGCAUCAGCCCUCUGAAGGAGCUGGUGUGUGCUGGCGAGUGCUUGCCCCUGCCAGUGCUCCCUAACUGGAUUGGAGGAGGCUAUGGAACAAAGUACUGGAGCAGGAGGAGCUCCCAGGAGUGGCGGUGUGUCAAUGACAAAACCCGUACCCAGAGAAUCCAGCUGCAGUGCCAAGAUGGCAGCACACGCACCUACAAAAUCACAGUAGUCACUGCCUGCAAGUGCAAGAGGUACACCCGGCAGCACAACGAGUCCAGUCACAACUUUGAGAGCAUGUCACCUGCCAAGCCAGUCCAGCAUCACAGAGAGCGGAAAAGAGCCAGCAAAUCCAGCAAGCACAGCAUGAGUUAGAACUCAGACUCCCAUAACUAGACUUACUAGUAACCAUCUGCUUUACAGAUUUGAUUGCUUGGAAGACUCAAGCCUGCCACUGCUGUUUUCUCACUUGAAAGUAUAUGCUUUCUGCUUUGAUCAAACCCAGCAAGCUGUCUUAAGUAUCAGGACCUUCUUUGGGAAUAGUUUUUCCUUUUCAAGUUUUUCAAGAUGUAGGUAUAUCCAUGAAUGCAAUUUGCAUUUAAAUUCCACGUAUCCUGUAGUUUUAAUUCCUCAUUGUUCUUAAAAGACUGUUGAUACUAUAAACAUCAGUGAAUCAUUAUAUUUUAAAACAGAAAAGGGCUUCUCAGAUACCCUCCAUCUACUGGCCCAUCCCCUCUCCUAAACAAAACUCCUUCAAAACAGGUUAAAAAAAAUAUGUUGUCAUGAAUCUUCACAGUAACAUUUCAGAAAGGUGCUUUUUUGGUACUCUUCAUGGGAACAGUUUAGCAGCCAUGAGUGAUCUUCCUUUGAAAGAGAAUGAAAGACCCUGUGACAUUUCACUUCAAAAAUAAGCCCUGUAGCUCUUUACGGUCGCAUAGUAUGAAAUUAUACCCUGCAUGCUGACCCUCGCUUGGAAUGGAAUGCCAGAAAUGCAUGGCAGCAGCUAAUAAGUAAAGCUGAUUAACUAUUUAUUUGUCAAUGUUAUUAUUUAAUGAGCUUUCACAUGUGAUUUGUUUCAAAACUUUAAUUUUUUAAUGUUUUGAAACUUUUUCAUGGACCUAAAUAUUUUCCUAUAUGAUUUGUGGUUGAUUAGAAAUAUGAAAUACAUGUUGUAGAUAUGUAAAAUGAAUAUUUUAGUCUCCUUAUUACAUAUAUGUUCAUGGUGAACUUUAUCAAUAGUAUGGAUCUUUUUAAAUCAAUAAGAUGCUUUGUAAAGUUGAAAUAAGUAAUACUUUCUUGUUUAAUCUGUGCAAUCAGAAGGUGUCUUGACCUUCAAUUCAAUUGGUUUCUUUUAACAAAAAUAAACACUGCUAAAAGUUAUUGUUGUUGCCUCUAACAUGUAUAAAGGGUGCAAAAAUUGUAGAAUAAAUGUAUAAGGGUAA